AAAGGGCAGCUAGUAUUCCCAUCCUUGUCUAACAAGCUGUAAGGAGAAGUUGUUUCUGAGAUCUGAGCCUGAAGAGAGGGAACAAGUCAGUCAGCCUUCGUGGUCAGAAGAUAUUGCCUCCUUCCAAGCUACCAGGCCAGGAAGUCCAUUCAGCUGGAAGCCGGGACAGCAACCUUGUUUUCAUUUAGGCUCCUUUCCUGCCACUUGUUCCACGAUGUAUGUCAAGAGUUAAAAGCUGUCUGAUCCGGCUGUAUUUGAAUUGGCAGAGCAGACCCUAAUUCAGUUAUCUGGUUCCUCCAUUGCAGCCUAAAGACCAUAGAACUCUAAAUCAGGCAGAAGGAAGGGAAGGUGGGAAAAGUACUGAAAAGCAAAAUCCCACAGGGAUCCAAAUGGUCCUCGAGAGAAUAAUCUUAUCCAGAAGCAAUGACCAAGUGGCACAUAAUUGAGCCCCAGGACUGGCCAACCAGAUGAAAAAUAGGCCAGUGGAGCCUACAUGGUAACUUACUGCAUUUGGUGCUGUGAUCCAACUCAUCUCCCCAUCCCUGCAGAGAAACCUGUGACCAUGAGGAGCAGCCUGACCAUGGUGGGAACCCUCUGGGCCUUCCUGUCCCUUGUUACUGCUGUGACCAGUUCUACCAGUUACUUCCUACCUUACUGGCUCUUUGGAUCCCAGAUGGGGAAGCCAGUGUCAUUCAGCACAUUCCGGAGGUGCAACUACCCUGUGCGGGGAGAGGGACACAGUCUGAUCAUGGUGGAAGAAUGUGGGCGCUAUGCCAGCUUCAAUGCCAUCCCAAGCCUGGCCUGGCAGAUGUGCACAGUGGUGACAGGUGCCGGCUGUGCUCUGCUGCUCCUGGUGGCACUAGCUGCUGUCCUGGGUUGCUGCAUGGAGGAGCUCAUCUCCAGAAUGAUGGGACGUUGCAUGGGAGCAGCGCAGUUUGUUGGAGGGCUGCUGAUAAGCUCAGGCUGUGCCUUAUACCCUUUAGGAUGGAAUAGCCCGGAGAUAAUGCAAACAUGUGGGAAUGUCUCCAAUCAAUUUCAGUUAGGUACCUGUCGGCUUGGCUGGGCCUAUUACUGUGCUGGAGGUGGAGCAGCUGCAGCCAUGUUGAUCUGCACCUGGCUCUCUUGCUUUGCUGGAAGAAACCCCAAGCCUGUCAUAUUGGUGGAGAGCAUCAUGAGGAAUACCAAUUCUUAUGCUAUGGAGCUUGACCAUUGCCUCAAACCUUGAGCUUUGAAAGAAGAUUGGAGAGGGUGGGAAAGGGGAGGAGGGAGCCCUGAAAAGAGGUACUAAGGAUUAGGCCAUUUGUCAUCUGACUGUCAUUAGCAUAGCCUAGUGUUUGCAUGCUUUUUAAACUAAUUGUCGUUCAUUUUCACUUAUCUUUAAGCCAGUAGGUCACUGGCUGUUUAUAAAAUUCAUCAGAGGAAACAUUCUCAGACAUUUACCCAACUGGCAAGUCGUGCUAACCCGAAGACCCAAAGUACCCCUUUAUGCAAAAUAGGAUCCAAAGCUAAGGCUGGGUAAGAAUAGUUGUGCAGGGAGGGAGCACGAGAUGGGCAGAGCUGGUUCCUACCACUCCAUUCACACAGUUCAUCAGUUCAUUCCCAAGUAUUUAUUGUCACCCCCAAACAUCUCUGGAGUACUACUGCUCAAUUUUUGUGUCGUUAUCAGGAGUAUACCUUGGCUCUUCCUUUUUUUCUCCUGCUUCCCCCCGCACCUUGUGGGGAAGCUUCAGGGGAGCGGGGGAGGGUGAUUCCCAGUGGUGGGGAAAACAUUAAUCAAGGAUACUUGCAUUUAGCCUGGAGCCCCUUCCUCAUUAUGCUUUAGAAUAUUCAUAGGAGUUCCAUUUGUAUUCUGGCUGGGUGAUGAGCAAAAAAAAUAUAUAGUAGCAAAUAUUCUCUCAUCCUUUAGAGAUAAAGAAAUGGUGUUCAUCAAAUGUACUGAGAAUAGACUAGCAUUUGUGGGGCACUCAAUAAAUUUAAAUUCAUGGUGACAGUGACAA